UUUUUUUUUUUCCUUUUUGAGACGAAGUCUCGCUCUUGUCCCCCAGGCUGCAGUGCAGUGGCGCAAUCUCGGCUCACUGCAACCUCUGCCUUCUGAGUUCAAGCGAUUCUUCUCCCUCAGCCUCCCAAGUAGCUGGGAUGACAGGCACCCGCCACCAUGCCCAGCUAAUUUUGUAUUUUUAGUAGAGACAGGGUUUCACCAUGUUGGCCUGGCUGGUCUCGAACUCCUGACCUCAUGAUCUGCCUGCCUUGACCUCCCAAAGUGCUGGGAUUACAGGCAUGAGCCACUGUGCCUGGCUGUGUUCCAAAAGUCUUGUACGGAAAGAGGAAACCUGGCAGUAAAGUCCACAGGGGUGUGUGUCACCCGCCGUGGCAGGACAGGGCGUGUGUCACCUGGCGUGGCAGGACAGGGCAUGUUGCCUGAGUGUGAGGAUCGCGCCCGUUGGCUCGCUUCCCCCGCAUUUUGGGUUUGAUCUUUGACUUUCGGAGGGAGAUCACAGGAGGUUGGCUCCCAAUCUGGUUCCCCUAGCUGCGUUUGGGAGGCCGUCCGUGUGUAGUGCUGAUAUGAACUGAAGGGGCGGCACCUCUGCCCUGUGAGUUUGCGCCCCACAUCGUGGGUGACUGGGCGGCACCUCUGUCCUGUGAGUUUGCGCCCCGCAUCGUGGGUGACGGGACGGCACCUCUGCCCUGUGAGUUUGUGCCCCACAUCAUGGGUUACUGGGCCGCACCUCUGCCCUGUGAGUUUGCAUCCUGCAUCGUGGGUGACUGGGCGGCACCUCUGCCCUGUGAGUUUGCAUCCUGCAUCGUGGGUGACUGGGCAGCACCUCUGCCCUGUGAGUUUGCGCCCCGCAUCGUGGGUGACUGGGCGGCACCUCUGCCCUGUGAGUUUGCGCCCCGCAUCGUGGGUUACUGGGUGCACUUGUUUAAAUCGUCUCCUGGUGGUUUGAGCACAUUCCCUCUGGUGCUGUCUUAAAGCUUCCCUUUGGAGACUUACCGGGGGUCAGAGGCCGACUUCUGAAUCCUCAAGGACAGUAAGGAAGUGAGAAGGAUGGAGGGAUCCGAGGAUGGCUGGAGAAGGGAAGGAGGUGGAAGAGAAGGAAGUGGAGAGGGGCGUACCCCUAAGAAGAGUUGGAAGGGGCCUUGCGGGUGGGGGGCUGUGGUGGGCGUCAGAGGUGGUGUGGAAGGUUGCAGGAGAAGAAAAGGCCAGUCUGAGAUGGCUGCAGACUUCUGGUUCCAAGUCUAGGACACUCGGAAAAAGGAAAACGAUGGAGACAGGAAACAGAUCGGGGCUUGCGGGGGUUGGGUGCGUCAGUGCCACACAGACGUUUUUCAGGGCAGGGAAACUCCUCUGCGUGACCCCACAGUGGUAGAUCCGUGUCAUCCUGCGUUUUUCCAGACUCAACAGAGCGUGCGGCAGCGGGAGAGCCCAGUGCACGCUGUUGACUCGGGGUGAUAGUGACCCGUCCAAGGAGGUUUAUUGACUGUAACAGAUGCAGGCGGUCACGCAGGACCUUCCUGAUCGGGGACCCGGGAGGCUUUCUGCUGACAGCGUUCAGCCUGGCAGGGAUGUGGCCAGUUUCUGACCCUCAGCCCGAAGGUAUCCUGUCUCCUUCCCGGUGGGAUCGAGGUGCAGGCCCCCGGAAUGUCAGCUCACCCUCAUUUAAAGUUGCCCGUCCCCCUUUUCCACCGCCCCUCUUUUCUUGUUCUAAAUACGAUUGCAAACAAGCGCAGUUAUCACAGUGAGCAGUGGCAGAGAAGACGAGAUCCUGGAUGCCCACUGCAGCUUAGCUGUAUUCUAGAAACUCCUGAAGUUUGGGGAGGGGCGGAGAUGCCGGCGCGCUUUGAUGCCGGGCUGCCGGGAUGUCUGGGCUGCCGUGCGUGUUUGUGGAGGCGCAGCUGCACCUGGCGUGCCCUGUGCUCUGGAGGGGCAAGCCGGAGUCGGCACCGAGCCUGCAGCCAGCUCUGGUGUUGUCGUGGAGGGGGGGGACCUCACUUCUCGCGGGGAGCGCCUUCGCCUGGGUCCCCGAGGCCGUCCCCAGGCUCUCUUCUCGGGGACCUGUUGAUGCGCGUUCCGCCCAGGCUCUCCUCUCGGGGACCUGUUGAUGCGCGUUCCGCCCAGGCUCUCCUCUCGGGGACCUGUUGAUGCGCGCUCCAGGGCGAGCCACGUGACGGCUGCCGCGGUGCAGAAAGCGCCCCCUUGCCCGGCCGGACGGCCCAGCCCGGAGCGAACGGGGAGAGGAGAGAAGAGGACCGGAGGGAGCGGAGGGCAGUGCAGGGAGCGGAGAAGGAGGAGAGGAGAGCAGCGCCGGGAGCAGCCGGGUCUGCACAGUCGCGGGUCGGGAGAGGCGGCCGCCCCCACCCCCGGCGCCAUGCGCCCUCCUCAGCCUGAGGAAUGCGCGCGGCGCGGGCCCCGGCCCCAGAGCGCCUGGCGGGCGACGCAUGGAGCGCGCUGAGCCCGGGCCACGCCUGCAGCGCCCCGCCGGCCCCGGCCCGGCCCUGCCCCGAGAGCGCGGCGCCCGGCCCGGCCCGCGGAGAGCCCUGCGCGCCGGCGGCAUGCGACUCCGCGAGCGCUCGCUGCGCCAGGACCCCGACCUGCGCCAGGAGCUGGCCUCACUGGCCCGCGGCUGCGACUUCGUGCUGCCCUCUCGGUUCAAGAAGCGGCUGAAGGCCUUCCAGCAGGUUCAGACACGGAAAGAAGAGCCUCUGCCCCCGGCCACGAGCCAAAGCAUUCCGACCUUCUACUUCCCCAGAGGACGCCCGCAGGACUCCGUCAACGUGGAUGCCGUCAUCAGCAAGAUCGAGAGCACCUUCGCCCGGUUCCCCCACGAGAGGGCCACCAUGGAUGACAUGGGCCUGGUGGCCAAGGCCUGCGGCUGCCCCCUCUACUGGAAGGGGCCGCUCUUCUAUGGCGCCGGCGGGGAGCGCACGGGCUCCGUGUCCGUCCACAAGUUCGUCGCCAUGUGGAGAAAAAUCCUCCAGAACUGCCACGACGACGCGGCCAAGUUCGUCCAUCUGCUCAUGAGCCCCGGCUGCAACUACCUGGUGCAGGAGGACUUUGUCCCCUUCUUGCAGGACGUGGUGAACACGCACCCGGGGCUGUCGUUCCUGAAGGAGGCGUCCGAGUUCCACUCGCGCUACAUCACCACGGUCAUCCAGCGGAUCUUCUACGCCGUGAACCGGUCCUGGUCCGGCAGGAUCACCUGCGCCGAGCUGCGGAGGAGCUCCUUCCUGCAGAAUGUGGCGCUGCUGGAGGAGGAGGCGGACAUCAACCAGCUGACCGAAUUCUUCUCGUACGAGCAUUUCUACGUCAUCUACUGCAAGUUCUGGGAGCUGGACACGGACCACGACCUGCUCAUCGACGCGGACGACCUGGCGCGGCACAAUGACCACGCCCUUUCUACCAAGAUGAUAGACAGGAUCUUCUCAGGAGCAGUCACACGAGGCAGAAAAGUGCAGAAGGAAGGGAAGAUCAGCUAUGCCGACUUUGUCUGGUUUUUGAUCUCUGAGGAAGACAAAAAAACACCGACCAGCAUCGAGUACUGGUUCCGCUGCAUGGACCUGGACGGGGACGGCGCCCUGUCCAUGUUCGAGCUCGAGUACUUCUACGAGGAGCAGUGCCGAAGGCUGGACAGCAUGGCCAUCGAGGCCCUGCCCUUCCAGGACUGCCUCUGCCAGAUGCUGGACCUGGUCAAGCCGAGGACUGAAGGGAAGAUCACGCUGCAGGACCUGAAGCGCUGCAAGCUGGCUAACGUCUUCUUCGACACCUUCUUCAACAUCGAGAAGUACCUCGACCACGAGCAGAAAGAGCAGAUCUCCCUGCUCAGGGACGGUGACAGCGGCGGCCCCGAGCUCUCGGACUGGGAGAAGUACGCGGCCGAGGAGUACGACAUCCUGGUGGCCGAGGAGACUGCGGGAGAGCCCUGGGAGGACGGGAUCUCUGAGAGUCUGUGUGGUCCGUGGCCGCGCUGGGUUCCCCGGAGCAGCGCCCGACGUCACUGCCGAGACCUUAAGGGAAGGCGCGCGUCCAGUCCUCGCACUGCUGCGUGUUCUGGUCAGAACGGAAGUGGUAGCCUCCACUGGGAGCUUCUGUGCUUUGGGAGAAUGUGUCUAAACUGUGGUCCUGUUUGUUCUCCAGUCCUGUGUGGACACCACGACCCAGUUGUAAACACAGGUCCCGUGCAGCUCGCUUUGGGGAAGAGGCGCGCCCGCCCAGGUCCUCUGUGUGUAGCUCACGCCCGGGGCUCCGUCCCGUCCUGGGUGGGUUUUCACCUGCACCGCAGGCCCCUCCCCCGGGAGCAUUCGUGGAGCCGGCGUCCUCAGCCAGGAGCGCGUUGCUGGCUCAGCGGCUGGAGCUCAAGGUCGGCUCAGGGGACUGUCUCGUGCUGGAGGUUGGCGGCCGAGCAGCCUGUGUUUCCCGGAAAACGGCCCAGGGCCUGCUCCGCGCUGCUGGCCACGUCUUCGCCAUCCCCUCGUUGCAGGUUCGAGGCCGAGCUCAGCCCUGUGGAGCAGAAGCUGAGUGCGCUGCGCUCCCCGCUGGCCCAGAGGCCCUUCUUCGAGGCGCCCUCACCGCUGGGCGCCGUGGACCUGUACGAGUACGCAUGCGGGGACGAGGACCUGGAGCCGCUGUGACGCCGCCCGCGAGAACGCCGCCGCGGGGCCGCUCCCCACGUGCCACCACCGGGCCACCGCGGCUCGUGUAAAAACUGUUGUGGAAAAUGAGUGCGUUUGUACGGAAUGAUAAACUUUUAUUUAUUCACA